GGAGCCUUCAUGGUCAAGUGACAUCAUAAGCUUAUAUGACAUACACAAGCCUCAGGACUUGGCCCAUGGCACUGAAGCAGGUCAUCAGGCCCAGCACAGAGACUAGAGCUGUGUUCUCACAGGGCCCACCACCCUUCCACCUCCUUGGCCAUUGACACCUGCGUCCCUGGCCCAGCUGCUCCCAGGUAACCCCCAAAGCAGCUGGCACAUCCCACCUCUGGUGUGGCCGGGGCUGCUGUGUGUCCGCAGGGCCUGCCCCGUCUAUUCUAGCUUGUUUGUCCUGUCUGAACCAGCGCCUACUCCAAGAAGCCUCUGCUCAGCCCAGCGGGGAUGCUUCUAAGCUCCGGACGAGCCUCUCGGAAGCCUUGGUGAUUGGUGGUGUAGUCAUCUUGGGAUGCAGAUGUCUUACCAACCUGCAAGAACAAAAACCCUGUGGCUUCCUCUGGUGCAGGGUAUUUAGUCAAUGUUUGCUGAGGUCCCGUCUGGUUCUGGCUAAUUGGCAGGGGUCGUCCACCCAUUCUUUCCCUGCUCUGCUGUCUGUGCCAGGAGAGACGGGGGCCAGUCGGCCAAGGGGCCAGCUCCUGCUGCCUGCUCCUCUUGGGCACGUGCGGGGGCCCCCUUUCUCUGAGCAGGGAUAGGGAUCAGUCUGCCGGAGGGAUGUGGUGGACAGGCCUAAAGCAUUUGGGGCGGGGCAUGCCACUUGAGCUCCCUAAAUCUGUCUCCUCAUAGGUGACACCGCUCCAGGGCCCCCCAGUGGCCUCUCCUUUCAGAGCUACCUAAAUUCUGGUCACUUCAGAGAAAUGGAGCACCCCCUUCUCCCUGGUCCAGGUGUGGACAGCCUGGCACACUGAGCACACCUGGCAUGGCUGGUAAUUUCAGAAAGAAGAGGGGCCGGGGUCCAGUGGGAAGCAGCGGUGAACCCCUCGUGAGUGGGCUUUGCAGUCCCUCCCCAUGCCACGGCAGAGCUGCCCUCAACACAGCCUUCCUCUUCCUCAUCGGAGAGCACACCCUGUCCCCUUGCCGAGCUGUGCCCUGUGCCUUCGGUGGUAUUUGAUUUUGGCUGCUACUGGCUUUGUUGGGAUCUGGAAGUCGCUUCCCCUGCGUGGUGCGUGGAGCACUGUAAGUCAGAUGAGGGAAGUAGCCAGGGUGAGGUGAGUACCGGGUGGAGCCGCCACUGAAGGGACUGGGUAGGGGGGCCUUGCCUCUACAUGAUGUGACACAGCCAACCGAGGACAGAGGAAGCCCCGUUCCUGGGGGUGUGGGGUGCACCCCUCAGGGAAGCCUGCAGUGGGGCCUGAGGAAAGGCAUCCUCCGCGAGCCCACGAGUCUGGUCCAUGAGCACCGUGACAGUGUCUGUGGGUAGAGGUGGACCCGGCCUUGUGUCAUCACCAGGACCUCUUUUGGGAAACCAUGUGGACAUCGCUUGCGGGUCCCCCAGGCUCUGCAGCCCCAGCAGCCUGGCUGCCUUUUGGGCAAGUGGCUUGAGCCACAGAGGACCCAGUCCUGUUGCAGCCACAUCCUCUGGGGGGGCCCGCCAGUGUGGCCGGCUUUCUCCACCCUACACCAGGCCUCCAGGUGUCCUGGUCGGGGGUGUCUGGGCCCUGGGUGGGCCCUGUGGACCUGUGAGGUCAGGGUCAGGGCAUCACUGGAGGCAGAGGGCUGAAGUUGUGGGUCUGGGUUCCCCUUGUGUGCACAGGCCCCUGCCCUCCAUGCUUGGUCAGGCAGCUACCCCCAAAACUGCUAGGACAGGCUGGUCCUGAGGUGGAUCCUGGCCCCUGUACCCUCUGGACAGCCCACCCGCCCAACCUUCUACCCUGCCCCAGCGGCGGCAGUGUUGGCCACAUCCUUCCCCUCCUGGCCCCAAUUGCUCUGGGGAAGUCCAGGCUCCGGAGCCUGCCCAGGGGCCCCCCGUGAUUUGGGCCCAGGACUCCACGUGGUUCUCUGCCUUCACCCAAGCCCUGAACUCCUCAGCUGCCAAAUCCCCACCCAUCUGCACAGGCUGUGCUCACCACUGCUGCUCCUGGAAGGUGCCCCUCAGUGGGACGCCCACCUCCUCUCUGGGCUUCUGUGUUUGGGAGCCCUGCUGCCCCCACCCUUGGUCAGUCCCCAUGUCCUGCUGGCCUGUCAGGCAGGGCAGAAAAUCCACCCAGAAAUGCUGAGCAGGAUGAGAGUCUAGUUGGGCCCAGCCUCAUUAUUUAGAAGGGAUGGAGGCCUAGGGAGCAUGCUUCUAGCCUGAGCCCAGCAGGGCCCCGCCCAUGUCCCAGGUCUGCACCAGGGACAGCUCCUGCCGAGGCCUGACCUGCCCCUUCUCCCUCAGGUGCUGCUGGUUGACCAGCCUCUGGCCCUAGGAGACCCCGUAGCGACUGAGGGUCCCAGCAGGCCAUGCAGCUUUGCCAAGGCGCCUCCGGCAUGGCGGCGGCCGAGGGGCCCGGCUACCUCGUGUCUCCCCAGGCGGAGAAGCACCGGCGGGCCCGCAACUGGACGGACGCCGAGAUGCGCGGCCUCAUGCUGGUCUGGGAGGAGUUCUUCGACGAGCUCAAGCAGACCAAGCGCAACGCCAAGGUGUACGAGAAGAUGGCCAGCAAGCUCUUCGAGAUGACCGGCGAGCGCAGGCUGGGCGAGGAGAUCAAGAUCAAGAUCACCAACAUGACCUUCCAGUACAGGUCGGAGGAGCGGCCGGUGAAGAAGCGCAAGGUGCAGAGCUGCCACCUGCAGAAGAAGCAGCUGCGGCUGCUGGAGGCCAUGGUGGAGGAGCAGCGCCGGCUGAGCCGCGCCGUGGAGGAGACCUGCCGCGAGGUGCGCCGCGUGCUGGACCAGCAGCACAUCCUGCAGGUGCAGAGCCUGCAGCUGCAGGAGCGCAUGAUGAGUCUGCUGGAGAGGAUCAUCACCAAGUCCAGCGUCUAGGCCAGCAGGCGGCGGCGGCGGCGGGGCCGGGCGGCUGGUGGUACUGCUCAGGCCACCCAGGGCAGGCCACUCAGGCCAGGCGGGCAAGGGGGCCGCCCCGCGAGCGGAGACCGCCUUCCACCUGGCCUCUGGCAGGAUGUCCCUUCUGAGGGGUAUUUUGAGGAACCCCCAGGCCCUGGGGACCGUGAGGCUCCAGUCUCCAGCAUGAAUGCCCUUCCUCGGACACAGGCCAGGGCCUCUGGGGUUCACUCCGAGUAAGAACGUCCUAGAGCCACUCUCCAGUGUCGUUACUAUCAAUGAUACUUGACGUGGCUUUGAUAUUAAACGUAUACUUUUUCAUUCUUGCCUGGAACGCACAGUUUGCUGUUGCUGGCUUGGUGAGGAUGCCCUGAUUGAUGGAUCCCGAAAAUGAAAGCAGAUGGAAACGGGUUGGGGCAGGCUGGAGCUGGGGGAGCUCUCUCCUGAAGGGAACCCUGUGUCCUCCCUCACCAGGACCUCUGCGUCUCUCCUUAAAUGGCCUCUGACGCCUGAUGAAAACCCCAGCGACCUUCCAGGAGGCUUUUAUUCAGCUCUGUUUGGAGCAUCAGGUGUUUCCACUGCCUCCUUAGCAAUGACACUAAUAAAAGUCGUAACACCUGUUCACAUGCA